GUUGCUCCGCAUGGUCCUGGGCUGUGGGUAGGGGCUAGGGCCGGGUCCCGGGGUGAGCCGAAACCUGGGGGUCGAGCGGGGCGGGGAAUGGGGCGCAGUGAGGCUGGGAGCCGGCCCUGAGCUCGUCUUGCAUAGGGGUAGCCAGGCUCGGGGCACCUGAGCUGGAGGCGGAAGCGUGAAAUAAGGACUGAGUGGGCAAAGAGAACCUGGGCUGAGACAUGGCCGCUUACCAACAAGAAGAGCAGAUGCAGCUUCCCCGAGCUGAUGCCAUUCGUUCACGUCUCAUCGAUACUUUCUCUCUCAUUGAGCAUUUGCAAGGCUUGAGCCAAGCUGUGCCGCGGCACACUAUCAGGGAGUUACUUGAUCCUUCCCGCCAGAAGAAACUUGUAUUGGGAGAUCAACACCAGCUAGUGCGUUUCUCUAUAAAGCCUCAGCGUAUAGAACAGAUUUCACAUGCCCAGAGGCUGUUGAGCAGGCUUCAUGUGCGCUGCAGUCAGAGGCCACCUCUUUCUUUGUGGGCCGGAUGGGUCCUUGAGUGUCCUCUCUUCAAAAACUUCAUCAUCUUCCUGGUCUUUUUGAAUACGAUCAUAUUGAUGGUUGAAAUAGAAUUGCUGGAAUCCACAAAUACCAAACUAUGGCCAUUGAAGCUGACCUUGGAGGUGGCAGCUUGGUUUAUCUUGCUUAUUUUCAUCCUGGAGAUCCUUCUUAAGUGGCUAUCCAACUUUUCUGUUUUCUGGAAGAGUGCCUGGAAUGUCUUUGACUUUGUUGUUACCAUGUUGUCCCUGCUUCCCGAGGUUGUGGUAUUGGUAGGGGUAACAGGCCAAUCGGUGUGGCUUCAGCUUCUGAGGAUCUGCCGGGUGCUGAGGUCUCUCAAACUCCUUGCACAAUUCCGUCAAAUUCAAAUUAUUAUUUUGGUCCUGGUCAGGGCCCUCAAGAGCAUGACCUUCCUCUUGAUGUUGCUGCUCAUCUUCUUCUACAUUUUUGCUGUGACUGGUGUCUACGUCUUCUCAGAGUACACCCGUUCACCUCGUCAGGACCUGGAGUACCAUGUGUUCUUCUCGGACCUCCCGAAUUCCCUGGUAACAGUGUUCAUUCUCUUCACCUUGGAUCAUUGGUAUGCACUGCUUCAGGACGUCUGGAAGGUGCCUGAAGUCAGUCGCAUCUUCAGCAGCAUCUAUUUCAUCCUUUGGUUGUUGCUUGGCUCCAUUAUCUUUCGAAGUAUCAUAGUAGCCAUGAUGGUUACUAACUUUCAGAAUAUCAGGAAAGAGCUGAAUGAGGAGAUGGCGCGUCGGGAGGUUCAGCUCAAAGCUGACAUGUUCAAGCGGCAGAUCAUCCAGAGGAGAAAAAACAUGUCACAUGAAGCACUGACGUCAAGCCAUAGCAAAAUAGAGGACAGUUCAAGAGGAGCUAGUCAACAAAGGGAAAGUUUGGACUUAUCAGAAGUGUCUGAAGUAGAGUCUAAUUAUGGUGCCACUGAAGAGGAUUUAAUAACAUCUGCAUCAAAAACAGAAGAGACCUUGUCAAAAAAGAGAGAGUACCAGUCUUCCUCCUGUGUCUCCUCCACAUCCUCUUCCUAUUCUUCCUCUUCUGAAUCCAGAUUUUCUGAAUCUAUUGGUCGUUUGGACUGGGAGACUCUUGUGCACGAAAAUCUGCCCGGGCUAAUGGAAAUGGAUCAGGAUGACCGUGUUUGGCCCAGAGACUCACUCUUCCGAUAUUUUGAGUUGCUAGAAAAGCUUCAGUAUAACCUAGAGGAACGUAAGAAGUUACAAGAGUUUGCAGUGCAGGCACUGAUGAACUUGGAAGACAAGUAAAGCAAUGGAUGGCUUCAAUAUCCUUGGGCCCAGCAAAAGAUAAUGAAGGGAAUUGUUGGAAAUAGAGAAUUGAAAAUAUAAACAUUCAGAUAGAACAAUGUCUGUUCAUUAAAAUUAAAAAGUAUAAGUGUCUAGGCCAGGCGUGGUGAAACCCUGUCUCUACUAAAAAUACAAAAAAAUUAGCUGGGUGUGGUGGCAGAUGCUUGUAAUCAUAGCUACUUGGGAGCCUGAGGCAGGAGAAUCACUUGAACCUGGGAGUCAGAGGUUGCAGUGAGCCAAGAUUGCACCACUGCACUCCAGCCUGGGCAACAGAGUGAGACUCUGUAUAAGUGUCUUAUAAAUACUCCUGAUAGCUGCUCAGUAGUGUGACCCUGAGAUAAGGGAUAUUGAAAGGCAUAAGGUCAAGUAAAAGAGUUAGUUCAAGCUGAGUGUGGUGAUGUGUGCCUCUAGUCCCAGCUAUGGGCUGAGGCAGGAUUGUUUGAGGCAGGGAGUUCGAGGCUACAGCAAGCUAGGAUCAUAUCACUGCAUUCCAGCCUGGGCAACAUAGCGAGACCCUAUCUCUAAAAAAGAACAAAACAAGUUAGCUCAGAUGCCAGUGGAGUCUGUGCUCCUUAGCUUUCUACCCUUUCCACAGCUCCUGAAUCUGACUCAUUUCUUGACUUUAUCAUUAUAGCUUCCACCCUUCCUGCAACCUCUACUGCCUGAUUAGAGUCCUAAUUUUACCCUCUCCCUCCCUGAUGCAUAGGUAAAGGCCCCUCUGUGGAGUAAGGAGAUCUUCAGAGCUGUUAGUGUAACUAAUUGAGAAGUAUUGUUUCCAUUGCGUGUUCCACUCAUGUUGCUUCUCUUGUGAACCAUUAACUUUAAUUGGAUAUUAUUUUUACCUGUUUCUGGACCGGAAGUCUCUUUAUUUCAUUUUGCCAUAGCUCAGGGCAGUGUUCAAAUCAGUAAGUGUUGUACAGGUUUUUAGUGUUAGAAGGGAUUUCAGAGUUAAUCUAUCUCCCAUCAAAGCAGGAACACCUUUUAGAACAUCACUGAAAGGAGGAUUAUCCAGGUAAUGCUUAAUGUUUCUAGUUAUUUGGGAUUUAUUAUCUAGAAGGGAUCCCAUUCCAUCGUUAGAAGACUUAAGUCUUUAGACAUGUUUAUUAUUAAAAAUUAUAUCACUUAUUGAGUGUUUAACAUGUAUGAGGUUAUUUAUAUAUUUAGUAUAUAUAUACUGUAUAUAGAGUAUGCAUAUUUCAUAAAAUAAUCAUAUAUGGAAGAUAGCGUCACAUUUUUAGAGAUCAGAAAACUAAGGCCUAAAGAAAUUAAGUAAGUUAAGUAGCUUGCCCAAGAGCACAUACCAAGUAAGAGGUAGAGCUAAGGUUCUAACUCAGGUUAAAAAUUCUGAGUUGAGAAAAAAAUCAGUUGAAGCCAUUUAAACAAUAAAAUAGCUUACUGGAGACUGGAAAAUUCAAAGGUAGUAUAGCUUCAGGAUUGAUUUAAUGUAAAAAUUCACUGUUGUUAGAUCUGUGGUUUUGUUUCUCUGGAAUUUUCCUGUCUGCGCUCUCCUCCACGUGUUCUUGUUAUUCUCAGACUGGCUUCACUUGGGUAGCCAGACAAUUUUCUGAAGCGCCUAGGCUUGCAUACCUAUUUCCCCAUAUGCAGGGGAAGAGAGCCGGUGACUCCUUUCUCAGUCAAUGAACAAAAUUUUUGAGCUUUGGGUCACAAUAAUGGUUAUUCUUGGAGUGAAGAUACUGAUGGGGAGGAAGCAUGAAGCAUCUGGAGUGCUAUAGAUAUGUUCCAUAUCUUGAUCUGCAUGGUGGUUACACCGGUAUAUACAGAUGUAAAAAUUCAACAAAAUGUACACUUAAAAUUUGGGCAUUAACUGCAGGUAAGUCAACCUCCACUCCUCUAAAGAUAUCCUGACCACCACUCUGAUUGGACCAAGAAGUUAGGUCAUAUGCUUACGUCUGAACAAAUUGUUGAGGUAAGGUGGUGGUUGUGAUGAAAUCACUAAUUAAGGCUUUCUCCUGAACUGGAGGUAAGGUCAGUAACACCCAACCUUAAGUAAGGGCUGCUACCCAAGUGGGGAAGAGAUGGAAGGGGGCAAUAGGGUGGUAAUUAUAAAGUCCUCACCUAAGAGUAUGUCUGGCAAAAAGGCCAAGAUGGGGAAAAGGCAAAUGAAUUGAAUGUCCAGAAUAAACAAAUCUAUGAAGACA